AGCCCCGUCCCGUCCCCGUCCAGCCCCCGUCCCGUCCCCGUCCCGUCCCCGUCCUGCGCCAGCGGCUGGAGCGGACCUCCCGUCGGCGGUGCCCGGGCCUGGGCGCGGCUCUGCAGGCGUCGCUGCCCGCGCUGCCGCAGCCUCUCGGCCCCGGCGAGCGAGGAGCGGGGCGCGGCUAUGGGAACCCGCGGGCCCUCCGCGCCGGUGGACACCACGCCCGCCAAGACCAUCGUGGUGUACCGCAACGGGGACCCGUUCUACGUGGGCAAGAAGUUCGUGCUGUCGCGGCGCCGCGCGGCCACCUUCGAGGCGCUGCUGGAGCAGCUCACGGAGCAGGUGGACGUCCCGUUCGGCGUGCGCCGCCUCUUCACGCCCACGCGUGGGCACCGGGUGCUGGGGCUGGACGCGCUGCAGGCGGGCGGCAAGUACGUGGCGGCGGGCCGCGAGCGCUUCAAGGAGCUCGAUUAUAUUCAUAUAGUUCCCCGAAAACCUGCAAAGAUAAGGAAGUUGAAGGAAAUCAAACCAGUGGUGCAUUGUGAUAUAAAUGUGCCUUCCAAGUGGCAAACAUAUCAUCGUAUAUCUCGACAUAUAAAUGUUUUUACAAAUGGAAGAUUAUUUAUUCCACCUGCAAAAAUCAUUAUACCCAAAUUUAGUCUGUCCGAUUGGGACAUCGUGCUGGCCACGAUCGGAGAAAAAGUCUUCCCUCUAGGAGGCGUUCGGAAAUUAUUUACAAUGAAUGGGCAUCUUUUGGGCGACUCAAAGGAUUUGCAAGACAAUCACUUUUAUGUUGCUGUGGGACUGGAGACCUUCAAAUAUUUUCCUUACUGGAAGUCUCCAAGGGUGCCCAGUGAGGUCCAACAAAGGUAUGCGAAUGUUGAAAAAAACUCACAGAGAAAGAAAAAAGUGGACUCCAAAGGAAAAGAACCUUGUAAAUAUGAUGGCAUACCCCCUAAAACACAGGAUUCUGUUUAUUAUGCCAAAGAAGAAAAGAAGAAAACAUUGGCAGAACCUUUAGUCCAAAGGGGUGCAGAAGGUGACGUGUAUAAAGCACCGACUCCUAGCAAGGAAACCCAAGGGGCGCUGGACGUCAAAGAGGAGCACAAUGUGCAGCUGGAGGUGCCUGUGGACCAGAGACAAGCUGAGAUAGUUAAAGAAGAUGAAGAGAUACAUGAGAACACCCCUGAUUUUGAGGGCAACAAGGAUAAAGAAGAUGCAAGGCUUUGUGAAGACGUUGAAAGAAAGAGAACACCCAGCACCUGCAUUUUACUGGUCACCUGGAAAGACCCUGUCACCUCCUAAAUCUCAUAUAGAGCAGAGGAAAUGCCACUGCAUGCAGCUCGCUGCCCGCUGUGAACUCCUAUGAGGAAGAAGGGAAAGAAAACCUAAUUCAAGUAAAAUAUGCUUUUCGGCGGGGGUUGGGGGAAGAAAAAUAAGAUAAAAAUUCUGCCAGUGCCCUGUAAUUUCAGAAGGUACAAUUUGCAUAAUGUUGGCAUGGCUUUCUGCGUAAUAAAAGCAUAGUUGUAUUUUUUACUGAAAUCGGCCCUAAAUGCUCUCUAAACUAGUCAAAAUGGUUACUUUCCAGUAAUUCUUUUAUCCAUACAUCUUACAUUAAAAUACCAUGGUUUUACACAUUUUGGUCAGCUUACUAAUGUCUGGAUUUUUGUUUGUUUCUUUGUUUCUGGUAUCUCUCAAGAACCUCAGCAAGAGUAAAAAAGUGGUUCUGUUUCCUGGUAAGAGAACCUAUGACCAGUGCUCACUCACGGAGACCUCUGUGUGAUGUAGGGCACGGUGCGGGUGGCCGCUCUGCGAGUUUCGCAGUGAAAGUGUCCGCCGCGAGGCCCCGUGAUUCACUACCUAGUAGGGGUGUCACCAAGCUUCCCACUGACAGGCAGCCUUCCCCAUGUGCUCAUGUGGACUUUGAGUAAACCAUGCUCUCAUGACUAUGCAUGGAGCCUUCUAAACUGUCUUGCAUAUGGCAGGUUCCAGGUCAGCUGACAAAUGAAGAUUUUGGCGUACCGUACGGUGGCACAAUCUCUCAGUCAACAAUGCGGUUUUGGCAGAUUUUCCAUUGUUCAAUUAUUUUAAUCUUUCACUGCAUUUAUUCUUAUAAUAUUUUGUAAAGAAAAGCUCGUGAAACUUGUGAUAAGAAGUACGAGUUUCAGACGGGAGGCUUUAGACACACAUGAGUAUCCUUAGGGGAGACAUUUUCAGCCACACUCAGGUGCCUGGUGGGUUGCAGGUUGAGUUCUGAAAGAAAACCAACAGAGCACACAGACGCACGGCAAGGAACGUCUCGUAGAUGAUUGGAUUUAAAAGGCAAGGUGAACGCAGAAGUUUUUGAAAAUGCAUUUUAAA